AUAUUUGAAAAGACUGGGAAAAGAGAGAGGAAACAAAUACCAUUUUUUUCCAAAAGGUGUAUGUAUCUCAGAUUGCCUAGGAAAGAAGAGAUAAGGUUAGAAAAAUUGACUGUAUUCUGUACUAAAGUAGGAAAACUUAUUUUGUUAGUUUUGAUAGUUAGUCCCUCCAGCUGCCCCUGUACUCUGAAAUCUUCUAAAUUUGUCCUAUUAAAAUUACUGGUUCUGCCCAAAUUUUGUUUAUAUCCCCAGAUUACCCAAACAGAUAUAGACUAAUCAUUUUUCUAAUUAUUAAACAAAUAUUUAUUGUGUGUCUACUAUGUAUUAGGAAGUGUAUUAGAUAUUAGAGACAUAUAGAUGAAAAUGCAUGGUACUAGUUUAAGAAAAGGAGCAUCUUAAUUUGUCUAGAGGAACUGGGUAGACUUAACCAGGAAGCAACACUGAAUUUAGACUUAAAAUAUUAGUAGAGGAUUGCUUAUUGAAUGAAAGGGGAGGAGGUUUUAAGCAGAGGAAAUCUCAUACUGAGAUUUGGAAAAUACUGAGGUGGGGCCUGGGGGUACACUGUGGUACACUGUGGGCAGCGUACAUAGUUUGUGAGGCAGGAACAUGCAUUCCAUUCUGAAAUAGAUGCAUUUCAUAAGAAGUAUUUAUAACAUACCUGGCCCUGUGUGUUACGUUAGAGGUAUUGUGGUAAACAAGAUAAAAACUAAUCCUUGCCCCGAUAUCCCGGUUUUACAGACUGCACGAUAAUUCAAAUAAGGAAAAGUCCAUUAUUAUAUUGUGUGGUGAUCCUUCGAAUUAAAAAAAAAAAGUACAAAGUGUUAUUGGAGCACAUAGGGAGGGUAUUGACUUACAUUUGGUAGGUCACAGAAGGCUUCCCAGAGGAAACGAUCACUAAAAUGACAUCUGAAAGAUGAGAAGGACUAGUCAGGCAAAAAGGAUGACAUUCAAAUGGAGUGGCCCAGGUAGCGAGGCAGCAUGUACAAAGGUUCAAAGCUUUUGAUUGGCUUUGAAUCUGGAACAGUAGUUUUAUGGGACCUCAAAUCAAAGAAAGCCGACUACAGAUACACAUAUGAUGAGGCUAUCCACUCUGUUGCUUGGCAUCAUGAAGGAAAACAAUUUAUUUGCAGUCAUUCAGAUGGCACCUUGACUAUAUGGAAUGUAAGGUCCCCUGCUAAACCAGUACAGACAAUCACUCCACAUGGAAAACAGUUAAAGGAUGGGAAGAAGCCAGAACCAUGCAAACCUAUCCUCAAGGUGGAAUUCAAAACGACUAGAUCUGGGGAGCCUUUUAUUAUUUUAUCAGGAGGUUUGUCAUAUGAUACUGUAGGAAGAAGACCUUGCUUAACAGUGAUGCAUGGGAAAAGCACUGCUGUGCUAGAAAUGGACUAUUCAAUUGUUGAUUUUCUAACGCUGUGUGAAACACCAUACCCAAAUGAUUUUCAAGAACCAUAUGCUGUGGUUGUUCUUCUAGAAAAGGAUUUAGUACUUAUAGACCUUGCACAAAAUGGAUAUCCUAUAUUUGAAAAUCCCUACCCUUUGAGUAUACAUGAGUCCCCUGUUACAUGUUGCGAAUAUUUUGCGGAUUGUCCUGUGGACCUUAUUCCUGCACUUUAUUCUGUUGGAGCUAGACAGAAACGUCAAGGUUACAGCAAAAAGGAAUGGCCCAUCAACGGAGGUAAUUGGGGCUUGGGUGCUCAAAGUUACCCAGAAAUAAUUAUUACAGGGCAUGCUGAUGGGUCAGUUAAGUUCUGGGAUGCUUCUGCAAUAACUCUACAAGUAUUAUAUAAGCUAAAGACAUCUAAAGUAUUUGAAAAGUCAAGAAAUAAAGAUGACAGGCCAAACACAGACAUUGUAGAUGAAGAUCCAUAUGCCAUUCAGAUCAUCUCCUGGUGUCCAGAAAGUAGAAUGCUGUGCAUCGCUGGAGUUUCAGCUCAUGUCAUUAUUUAUAGAUUCAGCAAGCAGGAAGUAAUCACAGAAGUCAUUCCGAUGCUUGAAGUUCGAUUAUUAUAUGAGAUAAAUGAUGUGGAAACUCCGGAGGGUGAGCAGCCACCACCUUUGCCAACACCCGUGGGAGGGUCCAACCCUCAGCCCAUCCCUCCUCAGUCUCAUCCAUCUACCAGUAGCAGUUCAUCUGAUGGGCUUCGUGAUAAUGUACCUUGUUUAAAAGUUAAAAACUCACCACUUAAACAGUCUCCAGGUUAUCAAACAGAACUAGUUAUUCAGUUGGUUUGGGUGGGUGGAGAACCACCACAACAAAUAACCAGCCUGGCAGUCAAUUCUUCCUAUGGACUGGUGGUUUUUGGCAAUUGCAAUGGCAUUGCUAUGGUUGACUACCUCCAGAAAGCAGUGCUGCUCAACCUGGGCACUAUUGAAUUAUAUGGCUCUAAUGAUCCUUAUCGGAGAGAACCCCGAUCUCCUCGUAAAUCUCGACAGCCUUCAGGAGGUGUGCUGAUUGUGACUUCUUGCAUGUGCGGCCUUUCUAGCUUAUAUUCUGAAUCUAUGAAAAAACUACGUUCUUCUUUUUUAACCGGUCUGUGUGAUAUUAGUGAAGGGACUGUUGUUCCAGAGGAUCGCUGCAAAUCUCCAACCUCUGGUUCUUCAUCACCACACAAUUCAGAUGAUGAACAAAAAAUGAAUAAUUUUAUAGAAAAGGUGAAGACCAAAAGCAGAAAGUUUUCCAAGAUGGUAGCCAAUGAUAUAGCAAAGAUGUCAAGGAAGUUAAGCUUACCUACUGACCUAAAGCCUGAUUUAGAUGUAAAGGAUAACUCCUUUAGCCGAUCACGGAGUUCAAGUGUAACAAGCAUUGACAAAGAAUCCCGAGAAGCGAUCUCCGCUCUUCAUUUCUGUGAAACGUUUACUCGAAAGACGGACUCGUCCCCUUCCCCUUGUCUAUGGGUUGGAACAACGCUAGGAACAGUGCUUGUCAUUGCACUGAACCUUCCCCCAGGGGGAGAGCAAAGACUUCUUCAGCCAGUAAUUGUGUCUCCAAGUGGUACUAUAUUGAGGUUAAAAGGUGCAAUCUUGAGAAUGGCAUUUCUGGAUACCACAGGCUGCUUAAUACCACCUGCGUAUGAACCCUGGAGAGAGCACAAUGUUCCUGAAGAAAAAGACGAAAAGGAGAAAUUGAAAAAACGGCGGCCUGUCUCAGUAUCCCCCUCCUCUUCUCAGGAAAUUAGUGAAAACCAGUAUGCAGUGAUAUGUUCUGAAAAGCAAGCAAAAGUAAUCUCACUGCCAACCCAGAACUGUGCUUAUAAGCAAAAUAUUACAGAGACCUCGUUUGUGCUUCGUGGAGAUAUUGUAGCAUUGAGUAACAGUAUCUGCCUUGCCUGUUUCUGUGCCAAUGGACAUAUAAUGACUUUUAGUUUGCCAAGUUUAAGACCUCUGUUGGAUGUGUAUUACUUGCCCCUUACCAAUAUGCGGAUAGCCAGAACGUUCUGCUUUACCAACAAUGGACAAGCAUUAUACCUUGUUUCACCUACAGAAAUCCAGAGACUUACUUAUAGUCAAGAGACCUGUGAAAAUCUUCAGGAAAUGUUGGGUGAACUCUUCACUCCUGUAGAAACACCUGAAGCACCAAACAGGGGAUUCUUUAAAGGCUUAUUUGGAGGUGGUGCACAAUCUCUUGACAGAGAAGAACUAUUUGGAGAAUCGUCCUCAGGAAAGGCUUCAAGGAGCCUUGCACAGCAUAUUCCUGGCCCUGGUGGCAUUGAAGGCGUAAAAGGGGCAGCAUCUGGAGUUGUUGGUGAAUUAGCACGAGCCAGGCUGGCACUAGAUGAAAGAGGGCAGAAACUUGGCGAUCUGGAAGAAAGAACUGCGGCCAUGUUAUCAAGUGCAGAGUCAUUUUCUAAACAUGCUCAUGAGAUUAUGUUGAAAUACAAAGAUAAGAAGUGGUACCAGUUCUGACAACCAGAAUCCAAUAAGUCCAACUUCAGCCAGAAGGAAAAAAGUUUUCCAUUUUUAUUACAUUCUUUAGGAAAGUUAACGUUAAAGGGAUGUUCGUCACUGAAUACUGUUCUUUCCUAGCACAGUCAUGCACUGUUUUACCUCAGUCAUGUGGCUUUAACUGAGGAGUGUUCACACGCACUCGAAAUGGAGUAUAUGGUGUGUGCCAGUUAUGAGUUGACCAUUUGGGAAUUAAACAGGUCACACGUGACAGAUGAAGAAACCAAGGGGGCUGCUGAGGAGACCUGGUGCAGGGACUAAUCCUGGAUCAUUCCUGUAUUAAACUUUCAUAUGCCAAAAGGGUUUGUGCCGUUUUAUCUGCCAUCAGUGUUUGACCUGUUUAGGGCAGAGGCAAUAAGUCAGAAGUCUUGAAGUUGAAAUAGUUAUAUGUGUGUCAUUGGACUGGAUUAUAAACAGCUGUCUUGGACUUUCCCUCUCUUAACACUGACUGGUCAUCAGUAUCAUUAGUGAAAAAGAAACAAAUUGUUUGUUAUCAUCUCUUUAGACAGAUAAGCUGAAUGGUGGGCUUUAAAUAAUAAAAACAUACACAUAGUUGACUUGUGUAUGAGCUACUCUUGGAUUCUUGUUAUUAUAGACUUGUAUUUAGUUCAUAUUUUGUCAAAAGCAAAACAAGAAGAUACAUCACUUUUCAUUGAAAAGAAAAGUGUAGAGCAUGACUGAAUUGCUCAUCAUUCUGGGAGUUUCCAUGUAGUGGCUAUGCAGUGUGGAAAGUGAGAAAAACCUCCAUUGUGGUGAGGAGAAUACUUCAAUGUCCCUUGUCCUUGUUCUCAUUAAUUCAGCUAAAGGUGGAUUUGACCAAAAUAAUGCUGGUUAAAUUUGUAGAAAUGUUGAAAUUGGCUGUGUUUUAAAUUUUGCUUGAAUUUUUAUAAAAUGUUUAACCAAAUGUACCUUUGCAUUCUUUAAUUAAAAUUGCUUAAAAAAAAACUUUCAUUAUUUCAGUAAAAUGCUCAGCUCCCUUUUCAAAAUGCCCUUUAUUUGCUAACUGUUCCAAUACACUCAGGUGAUGAGCCAAUUAAAUGUUAGUGCACAUGCUAUCGCAUGGAAAAUUACAAGCAUCUGUUGUCAAUAAUUAUAUAAGAGUUUAGUCUGAUGACCUACAAAAUAUUUUGUGUAGAAAUAUACUAUAAAUCUGUACAUAUCCUUUCAAGGUUUUAAAAAACCAAAAAGAAAGGAAAAUAUGUACACUGUGAUAACUAAAUUAUUUCUGUAUUGGAAUAUAAUACAAUUUGAGACCAGCAAUGGACAAUGAAUGAUUGUUUCAUAGAAUAGCAUUACGGGCAGGAAAGAAACCACCUAGUAGAUCUAGAAGUAAGCAAUCUCAGAAUACAGACUAAUCUGAGAUUAUUAUUGAUUGUUGUUAAAGCAACCCAGCAAAAGCAAAAUGGAAGCAUUAAAAUUAAUGUUAAUGAAAUUUAAAUAUUGUCUUCUAUAAAAAAUUCCUUUAAAUGAUUUUGUUUUUUCAUUAAGAGAUAAUCAGAGCACAAAUUGAUAGUAAACAGGAUGGUUGUUUUUCUAUUCUAUAUGAUCAUUAAAGGAAUAUGUAGGACAUCUUAACUUUUUCAUACAGUCUGUUAUGCAUAUUUUCCUCUACUUUUCAUUAAUAAAGCUUUUAUGUUUACAUUUUAUAACAUGCACUACUAGAUGCAAAAGUUUACAUCAAAGUUUACUUUAAAUAUCAUUUGGUAGGGACUAAAUGUGUGUGAUAGAGAUAAUUGAUCAAGCCAAAAGAAAUAUUUUUUAAAUAAGCCCUUUUCAAAAGUUUUUGAAUUUAUAGAAAGCACCAAUGAAUAACAUAUUUCUGUUUCGUUAAUGUCAGCUGCCUGAACAUUCAGCAGUUUAUAAAUUGCUUAAUUUGUGUUAUCUAUUAUCCAGUAAACCCAUAGUUCCAUGAUAUGUCACAGGAAUUGUUAGGUCCUAUUUUAAAGGUACAGUUUUGUGAAUGUCAUCAAUAAAAUCAACAGUUAUGGAUUUGAAGAAGUUGGGAAAGCAUUAUGUAGAUUAAUAUACUGGUUGGUUCCCUAUCUAUGUGGAAGGUCAUAUUAGCUGCAAUUAUUUAAUUUGCUGUGUUAUUUUGUGUUAUAUAACACAAAUAUAUUUGUAUAUUAACUUCAUUUUUACUGUCAUUUUUCCUGUUGUAUACAAAAUGAACUAAUCUUGUAAUUAUUUUCAAAUAUAGAAGUAUAUACAUUAGAUGGAUUUCCAAGAUUUUGUAAGAAAAUCUUAAAUCAGUGUUUUGAGUUAUUUAAUUUUUAAAUUAAUCUACAAAUUAUGCACAACAAACUAGAGACUCAGUUAGGAUUAGAAAGCUUAAAGUAUGUUUGAGUGUAGGAAAUAAGCUUCUCAGAGUUAUACUUGAUUCUGUCUGUAGAUAAGAGACAGUCUACAGUAAUAACUAACCCAGGGAAUUUACUGUAAUUUGAGAGGUAACAUCUCUAUUUUUUUCUUUUUAAAUACAGAAAGUAAUAGUCACCAGCAAGCCACGAUUUCAGGAAAACUGACUAAAAAAAAAAGUCAAAAUAGAAAAUAUCAGAAAAAUGAAAGAUUUUUGUGUGCCCUCUCCAUAUCCUCAUUGUUUUUGUUGCAUUUGUCCUUGACUCUAAAAUCACUGAAGUAUUCAUGAUUAGUAGUUUGUAAGUAGGAAGUGGUUUUUCUGUAUGUACCAUAUAUCCAGUUCAUUUCAGUUUUCAAACUAAAAUCCAUAUGUAUUUGCUGAGAAAGUUAUUUGAAAUCUUAUAUUCUGACAAAUUCUGUACAUUACAUCCAUUUGAAGUUUUGCAUCAUCUUAACACUUUUGCUUUGCAUUUCAAUUGUACAAAGUGUUUCCAAAAAAAUGGUUAUAGAUUCGACUGAGCUAUUACUAACUUCUCCAUUUGAUUUUUUAUGGAUGUGAAAAAUGCUGCUACUUGUCUAUGUUAUUAUGUGUAAGUAUAUUACAAUUUAAUUAAGUACAAUAGUUUAAAGAACGAAGCAAUUUUUUUUUUUUUGGCUUAGAACUUCUUAAUUGUAGGUUCCUCUGAAGCGAUUUCAUGUAGAUAUGUGAGUGUUUUAAACAAGUCUGAAAGUGUUACAUACUUUUAGGUUACAGGGGUGCUGGGGAGACAGCUGAGGAAAGGAAGAAUAUGUGGAAGACACCACGGAGUUCAAAGUUUUACCCUGAGUUCUAUCUUCCAUGUAUGUUUUGCUUAAGGCAUUUCUCAUGUGACAUUAGAAAAGCUAUAUCCAAAGGUAAAUUUUUUGUGGCAAAGAUUUAUUUUACACUUUAACUUUUGGGAUUUUAUUUGUUUCAGCAAAAUAAAGAGCACUGAACUUUAAACUUGAAUUUUUUCUGCACUUUUUUAGGUAAUGAAAACUUUUUAUUAUCAUUUAAUCCACAUUGCUCAGUUUAAACCAAGUGAUACAUGUGUAUAAAACAUACCAAAAUCAUGAAUAUGCUGCUAGCUGUACCUUAAAUAAACUGAUCAGUUUUAAAACCUUUAAUAGGGUUUUAUAUAGAUUUAAAAAAUAGUAAAAUAAUCUGCUGUAUGUUUCAGUGUUCUUGGUCUUAAAUUAUUGCAACACUUUCAGAUUUGUUUUAAGAUCAUACAGUAACAUGUUAUAUUUAUACAUACUGCUAGAAAAUAUACUUUUAGUUUUAAAAUGGAAUUUUUAUAAAUGUACUUUAAUUUUAAAAUGGUGAACUUGUUAAGUUUAAGUCAAAGUACUUAAAAAGUAUGUAUAUUAUCCAUACAAAAAGUUAUGUUUUACGCUUAUAAUAAGAAAUACUGGUAUCUCAUAUCGAGAUACAAUUAAUUUUAAAAAAUCAUACAUCAUUUAAAAAUCUUCACACAUGAACAGGAAAGAUAUCAUUUCUAUGCUUUAAAAAACCCUCUAUUGAGCAUUUUCAAAUAUUAAUUUUAUUUUGGGGGAAAAUGCCCACAACAAUAAUUGCAAGAUCUUUCUCAAUAGCUUCAGUUUGCUGUUGGAUGCCUACCUUAACUAUUGUUUUAAAAUAUAGAUAUAUAUAUAUAUAUUUAAAAUAGUUUUCCAGGUAUUUUCUUCUACCUUUUUUAAAAAUAAAUUUCCAAAAAUGAAAACAGAGUUUAUGUAUUUUUGUCAAUGAAGGUUUUUAUUUUGUAGUUUAUAGAAUUUGUUCCUUAUCAGUUUGAUACUUGAUCAACAUUCUUAGACUUUUUAAUCUGUAUUUACUUUGGGGGGAAAAAAGCACUCCUAUAUCUUAAAUGUCCUUCUUUUUUCUUUUCCCUUUUAGGGUAUUUGUUCUCUUGGAUUGAAAUUUAUGCCCACAGAUUUUUCUUUUCAUUUGAAAAUGAAUGUGAAGAUACUGUUUACAGCUUUUGUUAAUUGCACUUUUCAUCACUCUGAUCAAUUUCUUGUAAAGUGCUAUGGGAAUUAUUUUUCCUGUGAAUAUUAAUGAUUUUACUACUGCCUCCGAAGUUUUAAAAAAGGUUCUGUAGACAGAAAACAGUUGUUGCAACCAAAAACAACCAAAAAAAGAAAAAAAGGGAAAACUGGCUUACCUUUCUCAGAUGAAUUAAAUGAUUUUAAUAACUUCCCAAUUACCAGGGUUAUAACAUUGCUUUCUUCAGUUAUUAAUACAGUCAAAUUAAUUUUAACAAUAUAGGCACAAUUCAUUUACAAAUUCAGUACAGUAGUCCAGGGCUACAUGUAAGUGGUCUCUUUAUUUUAUUCUUUACAUCAGAAAAAUCAUGAAUGUCAGUUUUGCCAGUAUUUUACAAUGAGGCUUAUCGUUUAAAAUUUUAUAGUGUAUGACAUGUAAAUAAACCAGUAUUUAUUGUAGGUUGUUUGAUUCAGGCAUUUCAAAUGGAUAUAGGUUAAUGGCAAUGGAAUCCUAUUUAUUUGGUAGUUGGUUUUGUUUGUUUUUGUUUAUUUACUUUUGCUAUUUGUUUUGUAUUGUCUAAACUUUGCUUCAACUGAAGACAGUGUAAGGAGUUGAAAAUACAAUCAACAUAGCAAUGGAAAGCAAUGCAAAGAGGGUAAAUCUUGUUUUAAUUUUUUUAACUUUUUUUUUUUGUAAAUAAAUAGUACUGUGAUACUUUAGGUGUGACCUCUAUUCCACAUGAUAGUUAGAACCAGAAAAACACUUUUGCUUUCUAGUUAUACUAUUGGUUCAUUGUAAAUGCAUUACCAAAAGACAAUAUGAAAAAGAGCAAGAUUAAGUUUUUCUAACAUUGUCCACUUCAGGGGCAAGCAUGCUUGGUAUAGAGCUCUAGCUUGUGUAUACCUUAAACUGUAACUUGCAGGUGUUUUUCAGUUGCUGCACUUUUUAUUUAAUCUUGCUCAGUCCCAGUAACUAUCUCAAAGGUAAUUGCUGGAAUAUGCAUUUUGAAAUACGGUUUAAAAAAAAUCUGUGUAUUGUUUCAUCUAAAAAGAAAAGCACUAUUGGAAACACUAAAAACGUGUUAAACUUUGUAGUUAUUUUGCAUUCCUGUACUUUACAAACUGUCAUCACAGCAAAAAGUUUAAAAUUAGGUAAUGAAAUAUUUUUGUAAAUAAAUACCGUUAAGCUGGUAUUUUAAAAAAUGUAUUAUAAAUUAAUUAAUGUUUCUGGAAAAUGUUCAUAUAUAUGUAUAUGAAUGUCUCUUUAUGCUGAAGGGCUCUGAUUGGGCAAAAUAAAAUACUCUAAUCUCUCCUGAAACUAAA